UUUUUUUUUUGCAAAGUACUCUGUAAUUAAAGUAAAUGCAGAAACAGUAAGCACUGUUUCAAAAGUGAAUGGGAGAACCAACUGUUGGUGUUGCCCAAAAGAUAACAGAAGGUGUCCUUUUUAGGGCAAGGUCUUAUGAUCCAAGUGGCACGUGAGGGAACAUGACUAGAUUUGGCAUCAGGAGAGCUUAGCCCUGGUACAGGCUCUGCCAUUAACUCACAGGGUGAUGCUGAUAGCAGGGACAAGCUGCUUGUCUUCUCUGUUAGUUUCUUUGUGCUGCUGUAACAAAUGACUACAAUUCAAACAACAGAAAUUUCUUUUCUCACAGUUCUGGAGGCUAGAAGUCUGAAAUCAAGGCAUCAUCAGGGCAAUGCUCCCUUGAUAUCUCUCAGGAAGAAUCUUCUCAGCUUCUGGUGGUGGCCCCCAGCAAUCCUUGCUGCUCCUUGACUUCCAGAUGCAUUACUGCAGUCCCUGUGUCUGUUGUCAUCUGGCCUUCUUCCCUGUGCAUCACUGUGUGCCCUCUCGUCUUCUUUUAAGGAGACUAGUCAUUGGACGUAGGGUCCACUCUAAUCCAGUAUGACUCCAUCUUAACUCAUUACAUCUGCAAAGACCCUAUUUCCAAACAAAAUCACCUUCUGAGGUUCUAGGUGGAUUUGGACUUUGGGGGGAAGCCAUUCAACCCACUGCAGCUCCUCUCUGGGGUUUCUUCGGGUUUCUCAGAAAACUAUCUUUUGAGCUCUUUUUAGCUACAGCAUUCAAUAGUGCCAUGAAGAUUAUUCAGAAAAGAUAGAAACCUGAAAACAAAGCUUUAUUUACAAGAAAAAAGCUGGUGGCUCUGCUUGUUUUUGCUUUAGGUCCAGUGGCCAUUGGGACAGCUGCUCCGUGCAUCCUAGCUUCCCUUUACUGACUGCAAACUUUACUUUGGAUACAAGUUAAUACUGUUGGCCGUGAUCAGAAGGAAACUUAAAAGUUUGAGGACUUAGUAACAAAGUUGUGUUUGAUGAUAUGGCUCAGGUGAAGUAGAAAUGGAGAGCUUGGAGCCGAGAGCAGGGAUUUGGGGCCCAGUUUUCGGAAUGGCUUCCGUGUGAAGGAGUUACAGAGGAUGAGAUGGAAAGGAGGGCUGUGAAUCUGGAAAUGAGUCACAGCCAUUCAUUUACUUGUUCAUUAACCAACACAAAGCCAGUACAGGCUACUCUGUCAUCUUUGAAGAUGUUAGAUGUGGGAAAGUGGCCAAUUUUUUCCCUUUGUUCUGAAGAAGAACUACAGUUAAUUCGUCAGGCUUGUGUCUUUGGCAGUGCUGGCAAUGAAGUUUUAUACACUACAGUAAAUGAUGAGAUUUUUGUGCUUGGCACAAACUGCUGUGGCUGUUUGGGGUUAGGUGACGUCCAGAGCACCAUUGAACCUCGGAGACUGGAUUCUUUAAAUGGCAAAAAAAUAGCCUGCCUCAGCUAUGGGAGUGGUCCACAUAUUGUCCUUGCAACAACAGAAGGAGAAGUCUUUACCUGGGGUCAUAAUGCUUAUAGCCAGCUGGGCAAUGGGACAACUAAUCAUGGUUUAGUGCCCUGUCAUAUCUCUACUAAUCUGUCAAACAAACAAGUCAUUGAAGUUGCCUGUGGGUCUUACCAUUCUUUGGUGCUAACAUCUGAUGGAGAGGUAUUUGCCUGGGGUUAUAAUAACUCUGGGCAGGUAGGAUCUGGAUCAACAGUUAAUCAGCCAAUCCCUCGAAGAGUCACUGGCUGCCUACAAAAUAAAGUAGUUGUGACCAUAGCAUGUGGGCAGAUGUGCUGCAUGGCAGUAGUAGACACGGGGGAGGUCUAUGUCUGGGGUUACAACGGAAACGGGCAGCUUGGACUCGGCAACAGUGGCAACCAGCCAACCCCUUGCAGAGUGGCAGCUUUGCAAGGCAUCCGUGUCCAGAGGGUCGCCUGUGGCUACGCACACACAUUAGUAUUAACAGAUGAAGGCCAAGUGUAUGCUUGGGGCGCCAAUUCUUAUGGGCAGUUGGGCACUGGCAAUAAAAGCAACCAGUCCUAUCCUACUCCUGUCACUGUGGAAAAGGACAGGAUUAUCGAGAUUGCAGCCUGUCACUCCACACACACGUCUGCGGCCAAGACGCAGGGUGGGCACGUGUACAUGUGGGGCCAGUGCCGGGGUCAGUCCGUGAUCCUCCCGCACCUCACCCACUUCUCCUGCACUGACGACGUGUUUGCCUGCUUUGCCACGCCCGCCGUCACGUGGCGCCUCCUCUCCGUGGAACCUGAUGACCACCUCACAGUGGCUGAGUCACUGAAGAGGGAAUUUGACAACCCGGACACUGCAGACCUGAAGUUUCUAGUUGAUGGAAAGUACAUUUAUGCACAUAAAGUCCUUCUCAAGAUUCGAUGUGAGCAUUUUCGUUCGUCAUUGGAAGAUAACGAGGAUGAUAUUGUAGAAAUGAGUGAAUUUUCAUAUCCUGUUUACCGGGCCUUCCUGGAAUACCUAUACACAGACAGCAUCAGCCUUUCUCCUGAGGAGGCAGUAGGACUGCUAGACUUGGCUACAUUUUAUAGAGAAAAUCGUUUGAAAAAGCUCUGCCAACAAACUAUCAAGCAAGGCAUCUGCGAGGAGAAUGCCAUCGCUCUGCUCUCGGCUGCGGUGAAGUAUGAUGCACAGGAUUUAGAAGAAUUCUGCUUCAGGUUUUGCAUAAACCAUCUGACUGUAGUAACACAAACAUCAGGUUUUGCAGAAAUGGACCAUGAUCUCCUGAAGAACUUUAUCAGCAAAGCAAGCAGAGUUGGAGCCUUUAAAAAUUGAUCCCAUCUGCAGGAAAGUUUUUGAGCCUUUCCAUUUCCCCUGCAAAAGCCAGAGAUGAAUCACUUCUCUUUAAUUAAUAGUAUGUAUGAUGAGCUAUGUUUGGCUGAGUACUUGUAACUGUCAGAAGAAGGAUGGUGGUGAGUGGUCUUUGUCUGCCUAAACCCAGAGUUUAUGUAGAAAGCAUUGAAUGUUCUGAUCAGAUGUGACUAAGGUCAAGGAAAAAAAAUUGAAAUAUCUUAUUUACCAUUUCCUCUUUUUGAGUCACUUAAAUUGGACACCUUUGGUACCCUGGUCUCAGUAUAUGCUAUUCUGGCCCAAAUGUUCCAUUAUUCAGCUGGCUGAUACCACAUAGAUAGCUUGACAAGGAGUGCUGUCUGUCCUUACCACAUUUUCAGCACUCAGCACAGUGCCUUGUGUAUAAUAGGCACUCAAUUUAUUAUAAAUCUUCAGUAUGUCCUGAGAACAGCUUUAGUCAUGGAAUACUGGGAGAAGGAAUAACUUUCACAAAAUAAACUUAAAACAGCCUGUAAUUAUUGAGGUUCAUAUUCUUCUGGUAUAUCAUUCUGAGAAAUUGUGGCUAAUUUAGAACAUUGUUUAGAAUUGACAAAAGGCCCUGGCAAUUAAAUUGUCAAGGCCCAAGGGCUAAUUUUAAUUUUCUUUUUACUUGGAGUCAUUCAUUAAUUUCUCACAUGGGAUUAUGGAGUAUGAAGUAUUAUCUUUGAAUGAAAUUCCUGGGCUGAUCUGCCUUACAUAAUCACAUAAGGUCCUUUGCUUUUCUUUGUGUUAAGAGGGACUUGCCUCUGUAAAUGAAAAUGACAAUGUGCUUUUCUUGUAGUUGACUUUCAUGUCACUCACUAUAAAAUAGGUCUCUUAACCUGGCACCAGUAUAACUAUAAAGCACUAGCUGAGAAGGAACUGAUACUUACAUUUCAUGGACAGCAUUAACAAGAAUGAGAUAAAUUUGUACUUUUUAGAUCAAAACAAAUUACCUAAUUGCAAAAGAGAAACUGAAAUGGAACAUAGUCUCAGAUUCUUCUAAUGUGUAUCUCACAAUGUCAUGUAAUGUAAAGGAAACCCUUUUGGAAUUAGAAUUCUUGUUCUGAUGCUGAACUAUUUGGUAAUAAAGUGCUUAUUUGCAGAUAACAGAA